AGUCGCGCGCCCCUUCUUGGUUCGCUCGGUGCCCGCGCAGGCCCCUCGGGCGGUGGCGAGGAGGCGCCCAGGCGGAGGCGGCGGCGGGCGGAGGAGCGCAGGAGCGGGCGGCCAGGCCACCGCGCGGCGGCGGAGCGGGCCGCGGCCCGGCGCUCCUUCCCCACCGCGGCCCGACGCACCCCGGCCGCCGCCAUGAGCGGCUCCUCAGGCACCCCGUAUCUGGGCAGCAAGAUCAGCCUCAUCUCCAAGGCGCAGAUCCGCUACGAGGGCAUUCUCUACACCAUCGACACCGACAACUCCACCGUGGCGCUCGCCAAAGUGAGGUCCUUUGGCACUGAAGACCGUCCCACAGAUAGGCCUGCGCCCCCCAGAGAGGAGAUUUAUGAGUACAUCAUUUUCCGAGGAAGUGACAUCAAGGAUAUCACUGUGUGUGAACCUCCGAAAGCUCAGCACACACUCCCGCAGGAUCCCGCCAUUGUUCAGCUGAACAAGCGCCCUGAUGAAGGCGUGCGGGGUGAUGGGAUGGCCUUCGCCGUUCUCACCCGAUGUCUCGUUGUUCAGUCUUCCCUGGGUUCUGCCUCCGCCUCGCCCUUCCAGCCGCACGUGCCUUACAGCCCUUUCCGAGGGAUGGCGCCCUACGGCCCGCUGGCGGCCAGCUCCCUGCUCAGCCAGCAGUAUGCCGCCUCCCUGGGUCUAGAGAAGUUGGUAAGCCCUCCAGCCUCAGCCGCUGCUUCCAGCCCUAGCUCUUCUCCAUCUCCACAGCCCGUUUCAGAGCUUGACUUGUCCUCAGAGCCACAGCAGCUCACUGCCAAGGGGUGCCUUUUCUGUUUCAGAUCUCUGUUCACUUACACCCAGUCCCACAUUGUCCUGUUUAGAGUCCCUACAGGUCCUGGAACCUUGGAAAGGGAGGAGAUGGAGAGAGGAGCUGGUUUUCCAUCCAUCCCAGUCGGCAAGAGCCCCAUGGUGGAGCAGGCUGUGCAGACUGGUUCUGCUGACAACCUGAAUGCUAAAAAGCUGUUACCUGGCAAGGGCACCACAGGGACGCAGCUCAACGGUCGUCAGGCCCAGCCGAGCAGCAAGACGGCCAGCGAUGUAGUCCAGCCGGCAGCUGUGCAAGCUCAAGGGCAGGUGAAUGACGAGAACAGAAGACCUCAGAGGAGGCGAUCAGGAAACAGGCGAACAAGGAAUCGCUCCAGAGGGCAAAACCGUCCAACUAACGUUAAGGAAAACACAAUCAAAUUUGAGGGUGACUUUGAUUUCGAGAGUGCAAAUGCCCAGUUCAACCGAGAGGAGCUUGACAAAGAAUUUAAGAAGAAACUGAAUUUUAAAGAUGACAAGGCUGAGAAGGGGGAAGAGAAGGACCUGGCUGUGGUGACCCAGAGUGCCGAAGCGCCCGCUGAGGAAGACCUUCUGGGGCCCAACUGCUACUAUGACAAAUCCAAGUCGUUCUUCGACAACAUCUCUUCUGAACUCAAGACCAGCUCCAGGCGGACGACGUGGGCCGAAGAGAGGAAGCUCAACACAGAGACCUUUGGGGUGUCAGGGAGGUUUCUUCGUGGCCGCAGUUCUCGGGGCGGAUUCCGAGGAGGCAGGGGCAAUGGGACCACCCGUCGCAACCCCACUUCCCACAGGGCCGGGACUGGCAGGGUGUGAGGGUGCAGCCAAAGGCUCCUACUGAAGUGGCGCAUAACUGACGCUGUGUGUGUCAGGACGCGAGGAAAACGCUGCACUUACAGGGAGAGGUGGUCACUUUGUUUACGGAGUUUGGAAGAGACCCAUACUGCUACUUGUGUUUUGGACUUAACUGAACUUGGACAUGGUCUGAGUUAGAACCACUUGUUUUGGGGAAGUAUUCAUGGGUAACCUCUUUGAGGUCUCUUUAUCUGUGUUUCCUUUUUAGUUGCGCAUAGCCUAAUUCUAAGGUUUUGGUAUUUUGCAAAAAGGUUUCUAUAGUGAAAGCUGAAUCCUUACUUUGUGACUUUUUUUUUUUUUUUUAAUGACAAGCUUUGACUUUUAAAAGUGGAACCAAAUCUGUUGGCAGAGGUGGCAGCCAAGUACAUCUCUGUAACCCAGCUGGCCCCUGGUGCUGUUGGCCUGGCACCCCACUGCCAAGGGUGGGGUCUCAGGAGUCAGGCAGGGCCAGCACAGGGUGGCGUGGGGGGCAGGGGUGGGUGGGUGGAGGGCACGGAAGGGGUUUUCCCAUGGAUCAUGUUGUAUAAGUGAACCAGACCACCCUGAUGGCAUCCACAGUGAUGUCAAGGUUGGGGCUGGCCAGGGGUGGGUGGACUAGAAGCAUUUGGGAGUAGUGGCCAGGGGCCCUGGACGCUAGCCACGGAGCUGCUGCACAGAGCCUGGUGUCCACAAGCUUCCAGGUUGGGGUUGGAGCCUGGGAUGAGCCCCGGCAGCGCCUUGGCCCUUCUGUGGUCCCUGCCAGCCUCUGACCUGGGCCGGUCAGUCAUUGCUGGACUCUGGCCACACACUGGCGUUCUCAUCCACUUGGAAACAAGCCAGUCUUUUCUGCAAGGUCAGUUGACCAAGAGCAUAUUUCCCCUCUGUUGUACAUCGUUGUUUUGUGUUUGUGUUGUAACAGUGGGUGGAGGGAGGGUGGGGUCUACAUUUGUUGCAUGAGUCGAUGGGUCAGAACUUUAGUAUACGCAUGCGUCCUCUGAGUGACAGGGCAUUUUGUCGAAAAUAAGCACCUUGGUAACUAAACCCCUCUAAUAGCUAUAAAGGCUUUAGUUCUGUAUUGAUUAAGUUACUGUAAAAGCUUGGGUUUAUUUUUGUAGGACUUAAUGGCUAAGAAUUAGAACAUAGCAAGGGGGCUCCUCUGUUGGAGUAAUGUAAAUUGUAAUUAUAAAUAAACAUGCAAACCUUUAAAA